AGUCCUGGGCCCCAGCUCCAGAGCACUCACGGGCUGCCAGGGUGAGCAGGCUAGAAACUCACGACACCAGGUAGCUCUGCAGGUGCUGGGAGGGCAACUCAGCCCAGAGGAAGAGCAGGCUGGGGAGCCCUCACCGCCCAAUGGGGACUGACCCCUGGCCCCUGCCCCUCUCCACCCCACUGCCCUGAAGCCAGAUUUCCUGCUCAGCAUGGACAGGACAGCAAGAGGCUAACCCUCUGCCCAGGUGGAAGCUGACCCCAAGCCACCCUUCACCUGGACAGGAUGAGAGUGUCAGCAUCCCCUUGCUCAGCAGGUGUGCUUCGCCUCCUGGCCCUCAUCUUUGCCAUAGUCACGACAUGGAUGUUUAUUCGAAGCUACAUGAGCUUCAGCAUGAAAACCAUCCGUCUGCCACGCUGGCUGGCAGCCUCGCCCACCAAGGAGAUCCAGGUUAAAAAGUACAAGUGUGGCCUCAUCAAGCCCUGCCCAGCCAACUACUUUGCGUUUAAAAUCUGCAGUGGGGCCGCCAACGUCGUGGGCCCUACUAUGUGCUUUGAAGACCGCAUGAUCAUGAGUCCUGUGAAAAACAAUGUGGGCAGAGGCCUAAACAUCGCCCUGGUGAAUGGAACCACGGGAGCUGUGCUGGGACAGAAGGCAUUUGACAUGUACUCUGGAGAUGUUAUGCACCUAGUGAAAUUCCUUAAAGAAAUUCCGGGGGGUGCACUGGUGCUGGUGGCCUCCUACGACGAUCCAGGGACCAAAAUGAACGAUGAAAGCAGGAAACUCUUCUCUGACUUGGGGAGUUCCUACGCAAAACAACUGGGCUUCCGGGACAGCUGGGUCUUCAUAGGAGCCAAAGACCUCAGGGGUAAAAGCCCCUUUGAGCAGUUCUUAAAGAACAGCCCAGACACAAACAAAUACGAGGGAUGGCCAGAGCUGCUGGAGAUGGAGGGCUGCAUGCCCCCGAAGCCAUUUUAGGGUGGCUGUGGCUCUUCCUCAGCCAGGGGCCUGAAGAAGCUCCUGCCUGACUUAGGAGUCAGAGCCCGGCAGGGGCUGAGGAGGAGGAGCAGGGGGUGCUGCGUGGAAGGUGCUGCAGGUCCUUGCACGCUGUGUCGCGCCUCUCCUCCUCGGAAACAGAACCCUCCCACAGCACAUCCUACCCGGAAGACCAGCCUCAGAGGGUCCUUCUGGAACCAGCUGUCUGUGGAGAGAAUGGGGUGCUUUCGUCAGGGACUGCUGACGGCUGGUCCUGAGGAAGGACAAACUGCCCAGACUUGAGCCCAAUUAAAUUUUAUUUUUGCUGGUUUUGAA